CAGGCCCAGGAAGUUGAGUCCCUGGCGGGGAGGACGGGCAGGUGCGUCCGCGCUGCCGAGCACGAAGUCGCUGGAGGUGCACACCUCGACGACACGCUCACAGAUGGGAGUUCAGACACACACUUCCUGGCUUGCGUGCGAAGCAGGAUCGCAGGGCAAUAAUCCCUCCAUCUUCCCCGGGAGGUUCUGUGCCUGCAAGAUACACGGCACCCACUCGAUGCCACCGGGCCGCCACUGUCUGGGCCUGGGAUCUUGACCCACUUGCCUUCUGUACUUCAGGGUUUAGAGGCAGCAGCAGCAGCAGCAGCCGUCUUGGAUAACUUUUGAUGGAUUCAGGAGGCCUGGAGACCUCUUGUGUGCAGGCACCUGGACAUAAUUUUCAUUCAGUCCUGCCCAAUGUUCCGACCUGGACUGCGGUGCCGACGAGGAAACCGAGGCUUAGCGGGAUCCCUAAUCCAAGGCCACGACGAGUGAGCCUGCUGGGUUCAAGCCAGGAGCCUGUCCCCAGGGGGCAUUUGUCACAGCCUUACCCUCUUCCGGGAGGCGCAACGCUUACCCUCGUGGACCAACAAUCGAAUUAACAUGCUGAUACACACAUGGGGCGGGCUCCCCAGACCAGGAGGGCUUCUUCAAUCUGCUGAGCCACGUGCAGGGCGACCGGAUGGAGGGACAGCGCUGUUCACUGCAAGCCGGGCCGGGCCAGACCACCAAGAGCCAGAGCGACCCCACCCCCGAGAUGGACAGCCUCAUGGACAUGCUGGCCAGUACCCAGGGCCGCCGCAUGGAUGACCAACGUGUGACAGUCAGCAGCCUGCCCGGCUUCCAGCCCGUGGGGUCCAAGGACGGAGCACAGAAACGAGCUGGGACCCUCAGUCCCCAACCCCUGCUCACCCCUCAGGACCCGACCGCUCUCGGCUUCCGUCGGAACAGCAGCCCCCAGCCCCCGACACAAGCCCCCUGAGGGCCUGAGGCAUCCUGGGUCUCACUCGGCCCCCAAAAACUGAUAAAAGAAUAAAACACUUAAAUGAAUAACAA